AGACGGGCUGCAAUAGGGAGCCGGCCCGACGCGGACCGCUUCCCUGCAGUGCCCCGAGUCCCGGGCCCGCGCCGCCGCCGCCCGGCUCCGCUCGCGGCCCCUCUGUCUGCAGGCGUGCCCCGGCGGCGGCGGAGAGCCGUCCUCGGCCGAGGAGGCUGGGAAACGCGAGCGCAGGCGGCAGAGAGGCCUCAACGCCGUCCCUUUCGCCACCGCCUUUUCCUUGCCUCGCGCCGCUGUGCAUUUCUCUCCUUUUCCUUUGUUUUUUUGGCCCCUCGCGGGUGUGGGCAUUGUUGGUUAGCAAAAGUGCAGCCUCAAGAUGGCUGAUGGCAACGAGGAUCUGCGGGCUGACGACUUGCCUGGGCCAGCCUUCGAGAGCUAUGAGUCCAUGGAGCUUGCCUGCCCCGCUGAGCGCAGCGGCCACGUAGCCGUCAGCGACGGGCGCCACAUGUUCGUCUGGGGCGGCUACAAGAGUAAUCAAGUCAGAGGAUUAUAUGACUUUUAUCUGCCUAGAGAAGAACUAUGGAUCUACAACAUGGAGACUGGAAGAUGGAAAAAAAUCAACACUGAAGGUGAUGUUCCUCCUUCUAUGUCAGGAAGCUGUGCUGUGUGUGUAGACAGGGUGCUGUACUUGUUUGGAGGACACCAUUCAAGAGGCAAUACCAAUAAGUUCUACAUGCUGGAUUCAAGGUCUACAGACAGAGUGUUACAGUGGGAAAGAAUUGAUUGCCAAGGAAUUCCUCCAUCAUCAAAGGACAAACUUGGUGUCUGGGUAUAUAAAAACAAGUUAAUAUUUUUUGGAGGGUAUGGAUAUUUGCCUGAAGAUAAAGUAUUGGGAACUUUUGAAUUCGAUGAAACAUCUUUUUGGAAUUCAAGUCAUCCAAGAGGAUGGAAUGAUCAUGUACAUAUUUUAGAUACUGAAACAUUUACCUGGAGCCAGCCUAUAACUACUGGUAAAGCACCUUCACCUCGUGCUGCCCAUGCCUGUGCAACUGUCGGAAAUAGAGGCUUCGUGUUUGGAGGCAGAUAUCGAGAUGCUAGAAUGAAUGAUCUUCACUAUCUUAAUCUGGAUACAUGGGAGUGGAAUGAAUUAAUUCCACAAGGCAUAUGCCCAGUUGGUCGAUCUUGGCACUCACUAACACCAGUUUCUUCAGAUCAUCUUUUUCUCUUUGGAGGAUUUACCACUGAUAAACAGCCACUAAGUGAUGCCUGGACUUACUGCAUCAGUAAAAAUGAAUGGAUACAAUUUAAUCAUCCAUAUACCGAAAAACCAAGGUUAUGGCACACAGCUUGUGCCAGCGAUGAAGGAGAAGUAAUUGUUUUUGGUGGAUGUGCCAACAACUUGCUUGUCCAUCACAGAGCUGCACACAGUAAUGAAAUACUAAUAUUUUCAGUUCAACCAAAAUCUCUUGUACGGCUAAGCUUAGAAGCAGUCAUUUGCUUUAAAGAAAUGUUAGCCAACUCAUGGAACUGCCUUCCAAAACACUUACUUCACAGUGUUAAUCAGAGGUUUGGUAGUAACAACACUUCUGGAUCUUAAGGCUUCAUAAAUAAUGCCUAUGAUCACCUUGCAUGGACAGCAAUCCUGUAAACAUCACAGAGUGGCAUCAUUUGUAUAAUUAUAUGCAUUGUUGUAGUUUGCACCUGUUGGUUUUAAUGUGCAUGUGAAUGGCCUAGAGAACCUAUUUUUGUGUCUAAAGUUUACAAUAAAUGUAUUUAACACCAGUAGCUGUCCUCUAUUAAAGUAAAGUAAUGGUUGGGCUUUUUACCCUGAAGAAUGGUUGCUACAUUUUCUUUUCAGUAACUUCAGGAUAUGUAUCUGUAGAAACAUUAUAGUCUUACCAUCAUCAAAAUGCUGAAGUCAUUUUUUGAAAACAUUAUAGAUUUUUUUUUUUUUAAUGGCAAGAGUAGUCUAUAGUUAUGUAACCUAGUGUUGUAAAUACAAUAUAAUAAAGGUUUUUUUUUUUAAACAUUAAUAUUCACAUUAUGACGAAGCUGGAAAAACAAAGUGUGGAGGGACCAACAACUGUUCAGUACUUUGACCUUAAUGCUUCAGUGUAGGGGCUGGAGCAAGUGGUCAUGCUGAAUACAGGCAGGUGCUGUCCAGUCAAUUAAAAAGUUUUUUUUUAAUUAAUAGGUUUUAUAGCUCAUGAAGGAAUGGAAAUAAUGAUGACAUCAUUUUCCAUUCUGUUAAGAGACAGAGGAAAAGUGGGUUAGAGUCUUUAGUGGUAAGCCUAAAAUGCGCUUCUGGUAUUAUAGGUUAAGAUACUCUAACGUGCUAUAUUGGUAAUUAAUUACUAAAGGUGGAAAUUAAAAUGGUACAGAACUGAAUCAGAUUACAAGGAAAAAAUUAAGAUCAAACCUGAAGGUCUACAAAUGAAUAGAAAUGAUUAAGCUGAGUCAUGAGAAUUAUUACUUAUAUUUUACAUUUUGGUCUAAUAUUUUUUUCUGACAAGUAUCAAUGAAAGCAGAAGAAAAUCCACUCCAAUACUUAGUUUUCAAGACACAAUCCUAAAUAUUUAAACCCCUUGUAGCUGGCCUAUAAUAUAUAUAUAUUAGAUGUUAUAUACAGUAGACUUACCAAGUCAAUAGUUUAAGCAAUCAAGCCACUUCACUGUUCAGUUUCUUUACAUCAUGAAAUGAAUACUUGGUAUUAACCUCCCAAAUUUCAAGAAAAUGUAGAAUAACUACAGAUGUAUAUAAUUAGCAUUUAACUGUCCACAAAUACUUUAGGAAAUCCUAUCAUAGUGUUUCCUCUAUAUAAAACUGGGAAAAAAACAAGAAUUAAGUCCUUUUGGUGAAUAUAGCAAGGCAAUGUUUAGUUCAUUUGGCCUGUAAUAUAUAUAUUAGAUGUUAUAUACAGUAGACUUACCAAGUCAAUAGUUUAAGCAAUCAAGCCACUUCACUGUUCAGUUUCUUUACAUCAUGAAAUGAAUACUUGGUAUUAACCUCCCAAAUUUCAAGAAAAUGUAGAAUAACUACAGAUGUAUAUUAAUUAGCAUUUAACUGUCCACAAAUACUUUUGGAAAUCCUAUCAUAGACAGUGUUUCCUCUAUAUAAAACUGGGAAAAAACAAGAAGUAAGUCCUUUUGGUGAAUAUAGCAAGGCAAUGUUUAGUUCAUUUUUAUAAUGCGGAAAUCCUGAUACAUGGUGCUUUCAUCUUUGAACUUCCAAAAGGCUAUAAAAUUGGCUCUUCUCAAAUAUUUUAGAAUUUCAUUUCAGCUAUUUCCUUUUUACGUUCAGAAGAUUGGGUGCAGACACUUUCACUUUGCCAGGAAUGUUUCUUGAUAAAUCUGUGUCCUAAAAAAAGAAAAUUGCUGAAUAUCUUCACAUCCUGUAUGGUCAAUCAUGUUUCUUUUAUGACAAAAACGAAAAACAUUUCCAAACUUUUAGCUGAGAUGGUUUUACUGCUUCUAAUAAGACAGCAUUUUCUACUAAAAUAACAAAAAACUGCUAACAUUUUAAAUUGUACUGUCAGUCUCCACAUUCCUUUUCUGAAGGAGAACUUUACCUUUACGCUGCGGAAUAAGUCUUUUUCUCUUGCUGUUGCUUCUUUGGAAUGCAUGAAACUAUUCAAGGCUGUUUUUGCAGCUGUAAAUACAAAAAAGAGUAAGAAUAAUCUACUGUUAAGUCACUGAACUGUUUAAAAUCAUAAUUCAAAAAAACAAAUUUAAAUACCUUUUCCCUUUUUCUGCACUCCAGGAGUAAGUUUCACUUUAUAUCUUUAAAAAGGAAUUACAUGUGUUACUAAAUAGACGUUACAAAACAAUUCACAAAAGCCAUUCUGUCAACUAAUGGUAACUUACUUGUAGUUUGUCAUGGUGGUGUAAGGGGCACAUAUUGGAAUGGCAAACAGUAGUACAUCUUCAGGAUGUGGCUGGCCUGUCAAAGAAUCAAAUAGGUUUUCCUAAAAAGGGAAAAUAACAGUUACAAAGGCAAUUUAUACCGCCCUUUACAAAAAAUGCUAAAACACUUGAAUUAGUAUCUCAACAUAUUUUUUAUCUUUUCCUGAUAUACAUACCAUCUAAGCUGGAACAGUGGUACUUAAACUCUGCUUCAUAGUUCCAAAGAGUUGAAGACCAAUGUUUAAAUAUAUUCUUUACUACUUAAUUUUUGCCUAGCAUAAUAAGUAAUGAGAACAAUAAUUUUCAAAAUCCUACCUACAGUUACAUUUAAGAGAAAGAAGGCCCAGGAGCAGUGGUUCACGCCUAUAAUCCUAGGACUCUGGAAGGCUCAGGCUGAGGCGGGUGGAUCGCUUGAGCCCAGGAGUUCAAGACCAGCCUAAGCAACAUGGAGAAACACCAUCUCUACAAAAAAUAUAAAAGUUAGCUGGGUAUAGUGGGUGCCUGUAGUCCCAGCUACUCGGAAGACUGAGGGGGGGAGGAUCACCUGAGCCCAGGAGGUAGACGUUGUGGAGAGCCAUGAUCCUGUCACUGCACUGGGUGACACCAGCCUGGGUGACAGAGACCCUGUCUCAAAAAAAAAAAAAAAAGGAAAAAAACUAUUGGAUAUUACCUGAGUUGCAGAAACCUGCUGUGGAUUAAAAUGAUGCAAUAAUAACCACAAAUAGAUUUAAGUCCUAUCACAUGGAAAUGGGACUAAUACCUUGGCUAUACCACUAUUUCUCGUCCUGGGGAGAUUCUGCCCUCAGAAGACAAUGGGCAAUGUCUAGAGAUAGUUUUCGUUGACACGAUGAGGGGUGAGAAGGAAUAGGUAGGGGCUGCUACUGGGAUCUAGUGGGUAAAGGCCGAGGAUGUCGCUAAACAUUUUAUAAUGAAUGGGACAGACCCCACAACAAAGAAUUAACCAACCCCUAAUGUUAAUAGUGCCAAAGUUGAGAAACCCUGGGCUAGAACAGCCUUCUCUCUUACCCAUUAUUAAGGAGAAAUCCCAGAGUUCUUAUUUGCUGUGCUGCCUGUGAGAUUGCCCCCAUUUAUUUUACAAUAUGAAUAAACUUAGAUUUAGGACAGAA